AGUCUCAGGCCAAGAGCUGCAGGCUGGCAUGGCUGGGGGGAUGUCAGCGGAGUGCCCUGAGCCUGGGCCAGGAGGUCUGCAGGGCCAGUCCCCAGGGCCAGGCAGGCAGUGUCCCCCUCCCAUCACGCCCACCUCCUGGAGCCUGCCCCCGUGGAGGGCCUACGUGGCUGCCGCCGUCCUCUGCUACAUCAACCUCCUGAAUUACAUGAACUGGUUCAUCAUUGCAGGAGUGCUGCUGGAUAUACAGGAGGUUUUCCAGAUCAGUGACAACCAUGCUGGUUUGCUUCAGACUGUCUUCGUUAGCUGCCUGCUGCUGUCUGCACCUGUGUUUGGCUACCUGGGCGACCGACAUAGCCGCAAGGCUACCAUGAGCUUCGGUAUCUUGCUGUGGUCAGGAGCUGGCCUCUCUAGCUCCUUCAUCUCCCCCCGGUAUUCUUGGCUCUUCUUCCUGUCCCGGGGCAUCGUGGGCACUGGCUCGGCCAGCUACUCCACCAUCGCGCCCACCGUCCUGGGCGACCUCUUCGUGAGGGACCAGCGCACCCGCGUGCUGGCUGUCUUCUACAUCUUUAUCCCCGUUGGAAGUGGUCUGGGCUACGUGCUGGGGUCGGCUGUGACGAUGCUGACUGGGAACUGGCGCUGGGCCCUCCGAGUCAUGCCCUGCCUGGAGGCCGUGGCCUUGAUCCUGCUUAUCCUGCUGGUUCCAGACCCACCCCGGGGAGCUGCCGAGACACAGGGGGAGGGGGCCGUGGGAGGCUUCAGGAGCAGCUGGUGUGAGGACGUCAGAUACCUGGGGAAAAACCUGAUUUUUGGGGCACUGACCAUCAUGACCGGCGUCAUUGGGGUCAUCUUGGGGGCAGAAGCUGCGAGGAGGUACAAGAAAGUCAUUCCAGGAGCUGAGCCCCUCAUCUGCGCCUCCAGCCUGCUUGCCACAGCCCCCUGCCUCUACCUGGCUCUCGUCCUGGCCCCGACCACCCUGCUGGCCUCCUAUAUCAGUAAAGAGAAGCUUGGCUGGACGCGGUGGCUCAUGUCUGUAAUCCUAGCACUUUGGGAGGUCAAGGCCGGCCUGGCCAAUAUGGUGAAACCCUGUCUCUACUAAAAAUACAAAAAAUUAGCUGGGCAUGGUGGCAGGCACCUAUAAUCCCAGCUGCUUGGGAGGCUGAGGCAGGAGAAUCGCUUGAACGCGGGAGGUGGAGGUUGCAGUGAGCUGAGAUUGCGCCACUGCACUCCAGCCUGGGCAAUGGAGCAAGACUCCAUCUUGGGGGAAAAAAACAGAGAGAGAAGCUUACCAGGAGUUCCACAGUGAAGAAGGGGCAGAACUGGGAUUUGAGCCUGAGCUUUUCUGACUGUAAAAGGUGUCCUCUGAGCAUUGGGUUAAUGUGUUAAUUUGAGAAAAUAGGACUCAUUUAUUGCCAGGGCAUAUUGUGGGCCCAAGAAGAAAUAGAGCAAUUCUCCCCAGGUUACAGAGGAGGGAAGCAAGGCCCAGAUUGGUUAUGGCCAAUGUGGACGCUGCUUUAAGGGCAAUAAUCAUGGUAAUAUCAAGUGUUCCAAAUCCACAUCCCAUCACACCCCUUCAUGGGCCUCACACUCUGGCUGUGCCAGCCGUGUGGGCACACACACUUCCCAGACUUUGCACGCGUCCAUUUCUUCCACCAAGAACACCAGUUCCUCUUUUGUGCAUCCUGAAAUCCUCCUUCUGCAAGACUCAACUCAAAGUCCGCUUCCUCCAAAAGCCUUCCCCUACCACUCUAUCCUCACACCAGAAUUCACGUUCCCACUUGGGCUCAGCACCUGUUUGGGUCCCAUGAGGCACCAAGGUUUAUGGGGCCUGUCCACAGACAGGGAGCCCAAAGGGCAGGACCAGAGCCAGAGGGUCCCUGUGUGCAGCCGUGUCCCUGGCUCCCCAAAGCCCCAGCCCUGCCUGUCCCCCAACAUGGGAAAGGGCUACUGCUUCUGGGAAGAUGACGCCAGCCCAGCCACAAGCAGAGGGGCUAGACCUCUCCUCCUUUCCCAGCUCCAUGGCCCUGGGCCCUGUGGCUGCAGACACAGAUGCGCUUGCACAUGUUAACCAGGUUUACUGAGCAGACUGGACUUUGGAAAAGUAAACCAGCCACAACUUUAUUGUCCUCACACUAGUUUGGCUGCAUCUCCUACCCAUGGCCAGAGCCCAUUGCUUCUCUAGUCACACACAUGAACUAAACAGUCUGGUCCCACUGAAAUCAAAACAAC